GCCACUCCCAGGCUCCUCGGGACUCGGCGGGUCCUCCUGGGAGUCUCGGAGGGGACCGGCUGUGCAGACGCCAUGGAGUUGGUGCUGGUCUUCCUCUGCAGCCUGCUGGCCCCCAUGGUCCUGGCCAGUGCAGCUGAAAAGGAGAAGGAAAUGGACCCUUUUCAUUAUGAUUACCAGACCCUGAGGAUUGGGGGACUGGUGUUCGCUGUGGUCCUCUUCUCGGUUGGGAUCCUCCUUAUCCUAAGUCGCAGGUGCAAGUGCAGUUUCAAUCAGAAGCCCCGCAACAGAGCCCCAGAAAGCAGAGAACUGAAGUGCAGCCAUCAGGUGGAAGGCGGCAGCCCCAAGGGGGACGUGGACCCGUUCUACUAUGACUAUGAGACCGUUCGCAAUGGGGGCCUGAUCUUCGCUGGACUGGCCUUCAUCGUGGGGCUCCUCAUCCUCCUCAGCAGAAGAUUCCGCUGUGGGGGCAAUAAGAAGCGCAGGCAAAUCAAUGAAGAUGAGCCGUAACAGCAGCCUCGGCGGUGCCACCCACUGCACUGGGGCCAGCUGGGAAGCCAAGCAUGGCCCUGCCUCUGGCGCCUCCCCUUCUUCCCUGGGCUUUAGACCUUUGUCCCCGUCACUGCCAGCGCUUGGGCUGAAGGAAGCUCCAGACUCAAUGUGACCCCCAGGUGGCAUCGCCAACUCCUGCCUCGUGCCACCUCAUGCUUAUAAUAAAGCCGGCGUCAGAGACCGCUGCUUCCCUCACCUGCCUGCCUGUCUCCCUCCUCUGUCACCACCAGCCUCUCCAAGCUCAAGUACAAAUACAGCCGGGUCUCAUUUGUUUUUUCAA